GGUCAGCGUCGCUGCCGGUCUCCGGCGGAGACGGACUCUGGAGUUUGGGCGGCCCGGGCGGCCACUAGGUACUCUGAUAUUCCGUACUAAACACGUCUGCAAGUCAAGAUGUCGCACCCGUCCCCCCAAGCCAAGCCCUCCAACCCCAGUAACCCUCGAGUCUUCUUUGACGUGGACAUCGGAGGGGAGCGAGUUGGUCGAAUUGUCUUAGAAUUGUUUGCAGAUAUCGUACCCAAAACUGCGGAAAAUUUUCGUGCACUGUGUACAGGAGAAAAAGGCAUUGGACACACGACUGGGAAACCUCUCCAUUUCAAAGGAUGCCCUUUUCAUCGAAUUAUUAAGAAAUUUAUGAUUCAGGGUGGAGACUUCUCAAAUCAGAAUGGGACAGGUGGAGAAAGUAUUUAUGGUGAAAAAUUUGAAGAUGAAAAUUUCCAUUACAAGCAUGAUCGGGAGGGUUUACUGAGCAUGGCAAAUGCAGGCCGCAACACAAACGGUUCUCAGUUUUUUAUCACAACAGUUCCAACUCCUCAUUUGGAUGGGAAACAUGUGGUGUUUGGCCAAGUAAUUAAAGGAAUAGGAGUGGCAAGGAUAUUGGAAAAUGUGGAAGUGAAAGGUGAAAAACCUGCUAAAUUGUGCGUUAUUGCAGAAUGUGGAGAAUUGAAGGAAGGAGAUGACGGGGGAAUAUUCCCAAAAGAUGGCUCUGGCGACAGUCAUCCAGAUUUCCCUGAGGAUGCGGAUAUAGAUUUAAAAGAUGUAGAUAAAAUUUUAUUAAUAACAGAAGACUUAAAAAACAUUGGAAAUACUUUUUUCAAAUCCCAGAACUGGGAGAUGGCUAUUAAAAAAUAUGCAGAAGUUUUAAGAUACGUGGACAGUUCAAAGGCUGUUAUUGAGACAGCAGAUAGAGCCAAGCUGCAACCUAUAGCUUUAAGCUGUGUACUGAAUAUUGGUGCUUGUAAACUGAAGAUGUCAAAUUGGCAGGGAGCAAUUGACAGUUGUUUAGAGGCUCUUGAACUAGACCCAUCAAAUACCAAAGCAUUGUACCGCAGAGCUCAAGGAUGGCAAGGAUUAAAAGAAUAUGAUCAAGCAUUGGCUGAUCUUAAGAAAGCUCAGGGGAUAGCACCAGAAGAUAAAGCUAUCCAGGCAGAAUUGCUGAAAGUCAAACAAAAGAUAAAGGCACAGAAAGAUAAAGAGAAGGCAGUAUAUGCAAAAAUGUUUGCUUAGAAAGGAUUCAGUUUUGCUUAUUGUGUGUUGAUUGUAUAAAUGCAAUAAGAAAAUGUAAAGGUUUUUGUCUAUGAAUAUGAUCCCUAAUGUGUUUCUUUUGACACCUUAGUUCCUUACUGUUUACAGUUUAGGAGUACUGAUAGGGGUUCAUGCUUAAUAAACAUGUCACAAUACAGUAAGUAAAGUGGUUUUGUUUGUUUCUUUGAGAUGGAGUCUUGCUCUGUCACCCAGGCUGGAGUGCGGUGGCGCAAUCUCGGCUCACUGCAUCCUCUGCCUCCCGGGUUCAAGCAAUUCUCCUGCCUCAGCUUCCCAAGUAGCUGGGAUUACAGGCACGUGCCACCACGCCCAGCUAAUUUUUGUAUUUUUAGUAGAGAUGGGGUUUCACCAUAUUGGUCACGUCACGUUGGUCUUGAACUCCUGACCUUGUGAUCCACCCCGCCUUGGCCUCCCAAAGUGCUGGGAUUACAGGUGUGAGCCACCGUGCCCGGCCAAGUAAAAUGUUUUUUAAAAUGGUUAUGUGCAUUAUUCAUAAAAAAUAAUGGUGUCCAGUCUUUUUAAACUUGUAAAGACACAUCUUAUUGAAUAAAGAGAUGAGAGCUUAAGUUUGUA